CUGGUGCUUCCGACCGCUGCGCGCGGCUCCUGGGCUGUCACAGUCUCCCGUUGCCGCCGUCAUGUCCCGGCAGCUGUCGCGGGCCCGGCCAGCCACGGUGCUGGGCGCCAUGGAGAUGGGGCGCCGCAUGGACGCGCCCACCAGCGCCGCAGUCACGCGCGCCUUCCUGGAGCGCGGCCACACCGAGAUAGACACGGCCUUCGUGUACAGCGAGGGCCAGUCCGAGACCAUCCUUGGCGGCCUGGGGCUCCGGCUGGGCGGCAGCGACUGCAGAGUGAAAAUUGAUACCAAGGCCAUUCCACUGUUUGGGAACUCCCUGAAGCCUGACAGUCUCCGGUUCCAGCUGGAGACGUCACUGAAGCGGCUGCAGUGUCCCCGAGUGGACCUCUUCUACCUGCAUAUGCCAGACCACAGCACCCCGGUGGAAGAGACACUGCGUGCCUGCCACCAGCUGCACCAGGAGGGCAAGUUCGUGGAGCUUGGCCUCUCCAACUAUGCAGCCUGGGAAGUGGCCGAGAUCUGUACCCUCUGCAAGAGCAACGGCUGGAUCCUGCCCACUGUGUACCAGGGCAUGUACAAUGCCAUCACCCGGCAGGUGGAAACGGAGCUCUUCCCCUGCCUCAGGCACUUUGGACUGAGGUUCUAUGCCUUCAACCCUCUGGCUGGGGGCCUGCUGACCGGCAAGUACAAGUAUGAGGACAAGAAUGGGAAACAGCCCGUGGGCCGCUUCUUUGGGAAUACCUGGGCAGAGAUGUACAGGAAUCGCUACUGGAAGGAGCACCACUUUGAGGGCAUUGCCCUGGUGGAGAAGGCCCUGCAGGCCGCGUAUGGCGCCAGCGCCCCCAGCAUGACCUCGGCCACCCUCCGGUGGAUGUACCACCACUCACAGCUGCAGGUACAGAAUUCAAUGCCAACAGUUCUUUUCUUUCAAGACUUUAACCAUGUCACUCCACGGGGACGCUGUUUUGAGCCUUUGGUAAGCCUCAUCCUCCAGGACCACACGGCAGGCAGGCAGGACAGCCCUUACUUAGGUCCACCACACCCGUUAAGCUCCCUCCUGGAGGAGACAGAGACCUGGGACAGCUCCGGGGCGGGCGAGGCCGAGGGAUGGGGGACGACGGGGCAGGGAGGAGUCCCAGACCUUUGGGAUCUUCGCCACCCUUGGACCCCCUCACCCUUGCGGACUUGAGGAGUGUUAAAAUCUCCAAGACGCGAGUCACCGGUACGAAGCCACAGCCAUUUCGCUGCUUGCUCGGUGCAAGUGCAGACGGUCCUCGUGGUUGAGAGCGGAGUCCAGCGCGUGGGC